CAGGGACACAAAUCCAAACCAUAUCAGUAUAUAAAUAGUUUUGGUUUGGUCCUUGCUGGGACCAAACUGGGCUGAGGUGUGGACUGAUGAGCAGGGCAGAAAUCAGCUUGUGACAAGGUAGACAGCAAGGAGCCUGGUGGGUGAGGCCACCUGAAACACAGCACAUGCCUGCAGAACAAACCCCUCAAUGAUCCUAGGGCAGAAGCCACCUGUCUGGGAGCUUCUUUUCUACUUCUUGCCUAGGUGGGAAGUGAUCUGACAUUCUGAGCCUUUGGAGGUUGCAGAAAUGACUAGAGUGAUGAGGAUGAUAUAUAACAUGCUCUACCACGUAUCAAACACCUACUAUGUCUAAGAAGUGCUCUAAUGUAAUGGAUCACCACAACAACUUUGUAGGGCUUAUCAAUUCAGGACGUUAUGAACAUGAACAUCAUUACUAUCAAUAAUUAUUCUGGGAAGAAGGUAUAAACUGACCCGGGCAAACUAGGAUGCGUAAUUAUCCCACUUAGGAGGUGCUUACACUAUUCCCAUUUUAUAGAUGAGGAAACUAAGAAAAUAAAUAGCCAUUGUGGAUGCUUUUCUGUUUCAUGCCAUGAUGUUGGAAUGUCAUGUUUAGACACAUCUCUUCAUUGUUUCUUCCAAGAAAUCAGAUUAGCUGGUAGCAACUAUAUUAAACCAAAUUUCAGUAUGAAAAUGUCUCCAUUUUGCCUUCCUCCUCCUGCUCAGAAUGAUAUGUGGGGGAAGUCAUGGGCAUAACGUUCUGUAAUAGAAGUAGAAUUUCUUAAACUUGCUUCUAACUAACAUUCUUAAAAUGAGUCCAAGGAAAUAAGAAAUGAUCUACGAAUUUCAAAUAGAUUUCCCCAAACAUUCACUCUCAUUCAAAUUUGUGGAGCUCUCUCUGCUCAUUUGACAAUAAAAAGUCAUGAUGUUCUUUCUGCAGGAGAGGCCAGGAACAGAAUGCCCAGUAACAAGAAGUGCUCAUUAGAACAUCUGAAGCCCACGUGUUCUUUGGCUUGAUUAUAACCAGAAAGCCAGAUAGUUCUUUAGGAAUGUAAUUCACAGCUGUAUCAAGUACACCUCCUGCACCGAUCACUCAGGAGGAAUCUAAAAAAAGAAAAGGACGUACGCGUUUCUUGUAAACACGAGGCACCCCAAGAUAAGAAGACAGAUAGAGCAAGGGAUGGACAUGGUCAUCUCCUCAGUGAUUGGAGAAAGUUACCGGCUUCAGUUUGAUUUUCAAGAGGCAGUGAAGAAUUUCUUCCCCCCAGGAAAUGAAGUGGUUAAUGGAGAAAAUUUAAGCUUUGCAUAUGAAUUCAAAGCUGAUGCAUUAUUUGAUUUCUUCUAUUGGUUUGGGCUCAGUAAUUCCGUUGUAAAAGUAAAUGGAAAAGUUCUGAAUUUGUCAAGUACAAGUCCAGAAAAGAAGGAGACGAUUAAGUUAUUUCUGGAAAAAAUGAGUGAGCCUUUAAUCCGAAGGAGCAGUUUCUCUGACCGAAAGUUCAGUGUAACUUCCAGAGGUUCAAUAGAUGAUGUUUUUAACUGCAAUCUGUCACCCAGAUCAUCUCUGACAGAGCCUCUUUUGGCAGAAUUACCAUUUCCAAGUGUUCUGGAAUCUGAAGAGACACCCAACCAAUUUAUCUGAUUGAACUGAACAUUGUAGCAGUUGCUCCCGCACUCCAGGCCUGUGCUAGACUAUAGGCUGGGGGGAGGGUAGGAGGUGGGAGGCAGAUACUUCCACCUGCGUGUCAAUCUCCGGCUCCUCCAUGGCUUCUAUGGAGGACUCCUCUCUUCUGCUUCUGUGGAUGUGAUGCCCUGGCAGGCCCAGGGCAGCUGAUUCCCCUAAAACUUAUGAUUACCAGGAUGGAAAGGCCUUGGUCCCAUGGCACUGGGUGGGGCUGGGGGAUAUUCUCUACUUUGAACACUUCUCCAAAGAGGCAGAAGGGCCACAGAGUUCUGCCACCCUGAACAUUUUUCUCAGUUCCCUGGGAGUUUUUGUGGCAGCCUUUGUGGGAGUGGUCUGACUGGCUGUUGACCUAGCAUGCUUCAUAAAUCAGGGUUUGGCCCUCUGCUUGGAGCAUCCAACCCCUUGAACUCAAACCUGUCGAGCAAGGGGUUAAGAGUUCUGUUCUCUUGCCAACCUGGCUGGGCAAAAGCCUGUGCCAUCUUUCACUGGGAGGCAAAUAUGUUUUUCAUCCUGCCAUAUGACACCUAUGAGAAACGUUCACAGUGAGGAGUAGCCAGGUUGCUAGGACAGUAACCCUGCCACACACUGCCUGAAAUCGGAACUCCCUUGGCCUCCCUCUUAACUAAGUGACCCAUGUAGAAGGAAGCCAGGAGAUAUGGUACCGAACAAUGACAGGGGAAGGGUAUUGGACACGGCAGCGUCCUCCUUAUUGAAAACACAUUAUGUCAGUUGGGAAUUUUAAAUAAGCUUUUAGCAAACCUAACACUAAAAGCAAAAUAGAAGAAAGCUAUACCAUUACCAUAAUACAUUUUUCAUCUCAUGGCUACAAUGGAAUUCUUGAAAAGGAAAAAAAAAUCCUAUCUACAUAUAAAAACCUGCAUGAAUGAAUCACUACAUAUGCUUAUAAUGAGGAAGAGUUAUGGGUCCUGAGUGUAAUUUUUUAUCCUUUCUUAAAAAGUUUCUGUAUUAUGCAUUUUGAUAACACUACUGAUGAUCCUUCCACUUAUAUUUGAAAUGUUAUGUACCACAUUUGCACAAUUAAAACUUUUCUUAGCAUUCAACCUAGAAUUGAUUAAAUUUAUGACUGAGGCUUCA